AUGCCCCCCAGCACACACAUGAAGGGCGAGGCUGCCAGUGGGGCAGGGAGGAUUCUCAGGGGCGACUCGGGGCACUGCUCCUCAGAUGAGGAUAACAAGGCCUUUGAAGUGUGGCAGCAGCUGCCGGUCUCUGGCUCCCAGCUGACAAACUCCCCAUUUUCUCUUCUUUCUCCUGCCCAAUGGCUGUGCUUCGGCACACAUUUAGGUCAUGUGCAGAGCGUAUCUCACCUCCAGUGGGAGGGAAGUGUACAGGAAAGUCUGCGGAGUGUGAGAAACUCCAGGUGUGCUCUCCCCAUGCUCUCCGCUCCGUGCAGCCUCUCACUCCACUUUCUUUUAUUUUCUCUUUCCCCCUUUUUUUUUUUUGAGAUAAGAGUCUUGCUCUAUCGCCAGGCUGGAGUGCAGUGGUGCUAUCUCGGCUCACUGCAACCUCUGCCUCCUGGGUUCAAGCAAUUCUCCUGCCUCAGCUACCCGAGUAGCUGGGACUACAGGCGCCCGCCACCACGCCAGGCUAAUUUUUGUAUUUUUAGUACAGAUGGGGUUUCACCAUGUUGGCCAAGAUGGUCUUUAUCUCUUGACCUCAUGAUCCGCCCGCCUCAGCCUCCCGAAGUGCUGGGAUUACAGGUGUAA